GCGGGUCCGGGAGCCAGGCACGGGACCCGCCAGCUUCAGCCUCCAGGGCCUGGGCGGGCCGCCAGGUGAGCGCGCCCCAGAGCUCAAAAUUCGUAGCUGGCAGCCCUGCGUCCACCCGGCGGACUACUGGCCAUGGAGCCGCGCACAGGGGACGCCGCGGACCCUAGGGGGAGCAGAGGAGGCCGCGGCCCCUCCCCGCUCGCGGGCCCUAGCGCCCGGCAGCUCCUGGCGCGGUUGGACGCGCGCCCCCUGGCGGCGCGAGCUGCGGUCGACGUGGCAGCGCUGGUACGCAGGGCGGGCGCCACAUUGCGCCUGCGCCGGAAGGAGGCUGUUAGCGUGCUGGACUCUGCGGACAUAGAGGUCACAGACAGUCGCCUGCCUCAUGCCACUAUUGUGGAUCACCGGCCCCAGCACCGUUGGUUAGAGACAUGUAACGCACCUCCCCAAUUGAUCCAGGGUAAGGCACGUAGUGCUCCGAAGCCAUCCCAGGCCUCUGGUCAUUUCUCUGUGGAGCUGGUUCGCGGUUACGCAGGCUUUGGCCUCACCUUAGGUGGGGGCCGGGAUGUAGCUGGGGACACUCCGCUGGCCGUGCGCGGGCUGCUGAAGGAUGGCCCAGCACAGCGCUGUGGUCGUUUGGAGGUCGGGGACCUCGUGCUCCACAUCAACGGAGAGUCAACGCAGGGCCUCACCCAUGCCCAGGCCGUGGAGCGGAUCCGAGCUGGAGGCCCCCAGCUCCACCUGGUUAUUCGUCGGCCUCUGGAGACCCACCCUGGCAAGCCUCGAGGGGUGGGAGAGCCCCGAAAAGGAGUUGUCCCGUCAUGGCCAGAUCGCAGCCCAGAUCCUGGAGGGCCGGAGGUAACGGGGUCUCGCAGCAGCAGCACUUCCCUAGUUCAGCACCCUCCAUCCCGGACGACGCUCAAGAAGACCCGGGGCAGCCCGGAGCCUAGUCCAGAGGCGGCCGCCGAUGGCCCCACGGUUUCUCCUCCUGAGCGCCGCGCUGAGGAUCCCAACGACCAGAUCCCGGGUUCCCCGGGGCCCUGGCUAGUGCCCAGCGAGGAACGGCUCUCGCGGGCCCUAGGGGUCCGGGGGGCAGCGCAGCUCGCUCAGGAGAUGGCAGCCGGAAGGCGGAGACACUGAGCCUACCUCUGACAGCGCGGGGCUCACUAGUUACCGCCCAACCUGGAUCCGGCGCGUGUGGCCGCUGGGCACUUGGCACCUCCCCAAGAGCUUCCACUUGGUUUGGUCCCCCCACCCGCUGCUCAGUGGCUCUGACCACACUCCCCUCGCAGCGUCAGUGGUACGACCCUUCCAGCCGGCUAGCCUGCGCUUCUGGUUCUGGGAGGGGGAGGUAAUAAAAUGGUUCGAUCCGGUCUUGACUUGCCAGGCGCUCGAGGCGGGGUGGGGCUGCCCGGGCCACUCUGUAAAGGAGCAGGUGGGUCGAUCCUGCUUGAGUAAUCGCUGACGAGCUUCGUGCUGCUGCUUUCCUGCUUGCACAUGUUAUCUUUGCUUCUGCCGGUCCUCAGUCUGGCGUGCUUUCUUUUUCUCUUCGCCGUCUCCUGCUCCUCUCCUUAUUCAUUAAUUUCACCUUUUUGGAGGUGUACAGGGUCUCACACAUAAAUUAUUGUGCAUGGCAUGGAGAAUGCAGAGGUGAGCCUGUCGUGGCAGGACUGCACCAGUGUAUCCACAGUCCUGUCUCGGAAUCAUACAGACCCUCAGCUGACGUCGGGAUAGCAAGGCUAGAAGCCUAGAAGCAGGGCAGCUUCCUUCGCCAGAGGCCUGCGGUCUCCCACUUCCGGCCUAGUCUGCCAGCUUUUGCUGGCACGUAGGCUACCACUCUCCGGGCACCGGCUGGGGUCCUGGAGCCCCCUUUGGGGCGGAGUGGGGAAGGUGUGAGUCAGCGCCCCUGGACGGGCCGGGCUAAAAAAGGCUGUUAGAACCUUUGGGCCGUGCCCCCAUUUUCCGUACAUGGUGAAGAACUGCAGCCGGGCUUGUGUGCACACGCCACACACUGGGCGUUCCCGGCACGGGAGAGGCCCAGAGUUUCCUUCACCCUGGGAACAGAGCCCUACAGCCAGGGCUUAUAUGGCCAGCGGGACUCCAACCGGGGUAGCCGCGAGGAAGGCGCUGGCAGAGGACAGAAAUGUCCAGUCACCUCCGCUGUCACCACAUCCUGAGCACUCGGCCCCAUCCCCCCACAGGAGGGAAGCUGUGGUCUGACGGAAUGGGCAACUUUCGCCCCUGUGGGGAGGGGACGGGGAAGGAAGAAAGAAUUUAAAGGACCGGAAUGCGAGAGUCCAGGUGGCCUUGGAGAGGAAAGAGGAACGGUGAAGACAAGCUGCGAGAGCUGGGAGCUGGAGGGUGAAGAGGUGAACACUUGAGUGGUUAGAGCUGUAGAUAGACAUUGUGGGGAAGUGUGCCAGGGUGGCUUCCAGCUACCCCUGACUUAGAGCCUGGUGGAGGUGUGGUUCUUCAGAAGUCAGCAAAGGGCUCAAGAGCCCCAGUCUAUAAAUACAGUCACACCCAGGAGACUAAUAAUAGUAACCCCAGCCACCAUGUACUUAGUUUUAUCCCUGCUACUGGCUUUAUUGCAAUAUUUAUUUUCAUCUACAAUAGUUGCACAUCUACUCAACUAUCCGAAUAUGUCCAUUUCGCAGAGGAGGAAAGUGAGGCCCAGGGAGUGCAGAUAGCUACAGAGAGGAGGGUCAAAGCACGAUUUAAUCAAGGCCUGAUUCCCAAGUCUGUCCUCUCAAUUUCACCUGCAUUGACAAGUAUUAAUUGAACCCCAACUGUAUAUGUUGCACUGUGCUAGGUACUGUGGAGAUGCUGGAGGAACAAGACAUAAAAUUUCUUUGUGUAGCUGAUGUAUGUAAUGAGAGUAGACAGAUGUCAGACAAAAAAGACGAGAAAAUGAAUAAAUAAAAAACCAGGCCAGGCGUGGUGGCUCACGCCUGUAAUCCCAGCACUUUGGGAGGCCGAGGCUGGUGGAUCACGAGGUCAAGAGUUCAAGAGCAGCCUGGCCAAGAUGGUGAAACCCCGUCUCUACUGAAAAUACAAAAAUUAGCCAGGUGUGGUAGCAGGUGCCUGUAAUCACAGCUACUCGGGAGGCUGAGGCAGAGAAUUGCUUGAACCCAGGAGGUGGAGGUUGCAGCGAGCCAAGAUCGCACCACUGCACUCCAGCCUGGGUGACAGAGCGAGAAUCAGUCUCAAAAAAAAAAAAAAAAAAAAAAAAAACUUCAGGCCAGACAUGGUGGUUUGUGCCUGUAAUCCCAGUACUUUGGGAGGCGGAGGCGGGUGGAUUGUUUGAGCCUACAAGUUUGAUACCAGCCUGGGCAACAUAGACCUUGUCUCUACAAAAAGUUUAAAAAUUAGCUGGGAGUGGUGGCUCAUGCCUGUAGUCCCAACUACUUGGGACACUGAGGUGGGAGGAUCACUUGAGCCUGGGAGGUCAAGGCUGCAGUGAGCCAUGAUUGCACCAUUCCACUCUAGCUGGAGUGACAGUGAGACCUUAUCUC